CGCCCAUCUGCCUCCCCUUCUAGCCCAGGUGCUUCUGGAAGGGCAGGAUUUUCCUCUACUUCAUCUUUAUGCCUUUAACAGUGUCUUGCAUAAAAGAGAGACACUCAGUGAGUAUUUGUGGAAGGAAGGAGGGAUAGGAGGAGGAGAACUCCCACUUGUCCAGAUCCAUCUGGGGGUUUAAAUCUUAACCUUUUCUUUUAUGAUUGAUGCAUAUCUGAAGAAGAGUCAGAGAAAAAUAGAAAUCUCAAGUCACUGCUGUAGGAUAUACAGGGGCGGAAAAGUUGUGGCACCUUUCUUUGCCCAUCAGAGGAGUCACAGCUGACACUCCUACAAGACAGGUUAACAAGAGGAGAGUGGACACAUUUAUUUAAUCAAAGACUUGUGUGACACAGAAGCCUUCAGAAAUGAAGACCCAAGACCCAGGGAAAGCCGUCUAUUUUUAUGCUUAGGUUUGUCAAAGGACAGACAGCCCUGUAGAAAUGGGAUUGGACAAAGGGGGUUUGAUCUAAGGUAACAGACUGAGGCAGGAGAAUGGCAUGAACCUGGGAGGUGGUGCUUGCAGUGAGCAGAGAUCACGCCACUGCACUCCAGCCUGGGCGACAGAGCGAGACUCUGACUCAAAAAGAAACCUCCACUUACUCUCAGAGGUAUCUUUACUCUCCGAGACCCUUUAAAAUUCUUGACCUUUCUUUUACAUCAGGCAAUUGGCAUCACUAGUGCCAGUUUAUUUUUAGAUAUAAAUGUAUGUCUGUUUGAAAAAUAAACUUUACAUCCAAAAGAGAAUGACUUGGCAAUGAAGUAAAACUGGAUCUAAUGGUAAAGGCUCAGCCCACCCUUCCUAGAUGGAUAAAAUCCAUUUUCUCUAGCCCUGGUUCGAAUGUGUCCCAUCACUUGUGAGUCCAGACUGGCAACAAAAGGUGCUGAUCUAAAAGAAGUUAUCGUCCAGUGGCAGGGUCUGGGGAAGGGGCGGCAGGCGCCAUGUCCAGCCACGAAGGUGGCAAGAAGAAGGCACUGAAACAGCCCAAGAAGCAGGCCAAGGAGAUGGACGAGGAAGAGAAGGCUUUCAAGCAGAAACAAAAAGAGGAGCAGAAGAAACUCGAGGUGCUAAAAGCGAAGGUCGUGGGGAAGGGGCCUCUGGCCACAGGUGGAAUUAAGAAAUCUGGCAAAAAAUAAGCUGUUCCUUGUGCCUAAGGAGACGGUGACCCUUUAUUUCAUCCGUAUUUAAACCUCUCUAUUCCCUCCUAUAAUAUCUUUUGCCACCUAUAGUUGGAAUUAAGUGUCGUCUUGGAGCUGUUGUACAUUUAAGAAUAAACUUUUGUAAAAAAAAAAAAAAAAAAAUCUUCCAGUGGCUCAUCAUCUCUUUAGUUGUUUUCACUAAGUCAUUCCUACCAUAACUGUGAAUUUAAAGUAAAACCAGCUCAGAAUCUUGCCAGAAUCUGCUCUUUGGUCGUUGUUCUACCCUAAACUUUGUAUCACCUGAAAUUAAACCAACUCAUUUGAAAGAAAAAA